AUUGCGGAUCGGGUCGGCGCCAUUUUGGGACUGAGACUGGUUGUGGGGGAGGGAAAAGCGGCAAAAGGGGAUUAUUCAAAGUACCGAAAACCUUCUCCCGGGAUCAGGCGCGGCGGCACCCCCAGGCCAGGGGCACCUCUGGUGGGGCAGAAGGUGAUUGAAUUACUCAGAUAUGAAGAUCAUCAUCUAGGUUUUGUGUAAAAGGCCCUGGAUAUUUUAAGUGGCCAUUUUGGAUUUACAGUGUUUUUGGAUAAUUUUGCCCCAGAAGUUUAUUAAAAUUGGCAAGAAUCGUCUGUGAAGUGAAUUGAUAGUAGUGAACAAUUCAGCAAGCUACUUAAAAAGAGACCCAGGCAGCAUUUCUUCAGUAUUUUGGUUCAAACGGAUUAUAUAACUGGUUACAGUAUUUCAGCUGGUGGUAAUUUUUGCCUCCCCUUCCCCCACCCCGUUGUUGGGGUUCUUCAGCCGAAACUGAGAGACGUUGAUUUGUGUACUGAGUAGUUUCAGCAGUUUCAAAUGACUGAGUAUUGCUGAAGUUUCAUGGCAGUUUAUUUUUACCUUUAUUGAAAGUUUUAGGAAUUUUUGACUUCAGCUCUUUCAUGUCACAAUGGGACACUUUUUCUGAAUGAAGAGAUUGAAAGAAUACAGAGUUUUUUUCCUUUUAUCUUUUAUUUACGUGGAAAUUUAAGAUGUUGCAGUUUUCCGGCAGCAUGGUAGUAUUGAGAUAGCUAUGUGUGUCUCUGUAUAUGCUGAUGUUUAGGAAUGCUCUUCAGAUGUGAAAUUUUCUUUUUGUUUUUGCUUUUUGGCUCGUAAAUUGGAUAUUUCAUCUGGAGUGGACAAGUACAACAGUGGCAAGUACAUGGAAUAAUAAAGAAGACUUUGAUCUUAAAUCUAAAGAACUUGGCUAAUUCGGGAGAUAGCCAUAUGAAAACUUUAAAACAGAAGUAUGGGUAGCUGACUUGAAGUAACUCUAUGUCAAAUAGUCGUAGGUUAAGUAUCUUCAAAGAACUUCGAUAUUAUUUCAGAGGAUACAAAAUAAAAAUACAAACUGGAAAAUAAAGAUUACAGAGAAAAAACCAACACCUUCCUGUGCAGUCCUGUUGGAAUUUGUAAGUACUAUUAUGGGACUUGCCAUGAGGUGUUGAAGCCUUGUUUCACUGAGUUGGAGAGACUGGACCUAAAUGGCGCAGCAUGACUUUGCUCCAGCCUGGCUUAAUUUCCCUACUCCACCAUCAUCAACAAAGUCGUCAUUGAAUUUUGAGAAGCAUUCUGAAAACUUUGCAUGGACAGAGAAUCGUUAUGAUGUGAACCGUCGACGACACAACUCUUCAGAUGGCUUUGAUUCUGCUAUUGGGCGUCCUAAUGGAGGUAACUUUGGAAGGAAAGAAAAAAAUGGAUGGCGUACACAUGGAAGAAAUGGUACAGAAAACAUAAAUCAUCGAGGUGGAUACCAUGGUGGAAGUUCCCGUUCUCGUAGCAGUAUUUUCCAUGCAGGAAAAAGCCAAGGACUACAUGAAAACAACAUACCUGACAAUGAAACCGGGAGGAAAGAAGACAAGAGAGAACGCAAACAGUUUGAAGCUGAGGAUUUUCCGUCUUUAAAUCCUGAGUAUGAGAGAGAACCAAAUCACAAUAAGUCUUUAGCUGCAGGUGUGUGGGGCCUACACGCCCAGACACACACAUACCCAACCAAAAAAAUCUCCCAAGCUCCUCUCUUAGAAUAUCCUCCGAAUCCUAAAUCUAGAGCUCCAAGGAUGCUGGUCAUUAAGAAAGGUAAUACAAAAGACUUACAGCUAUCUGGAUUCCCAGUAGUAGGAAAUCUUCCGUCACAGCCAGUUAAGAAUGGAACUGGUCCAAGUGUUUAUAAAGGUUUAGUCCCUAAACCUGCUGCUCCACCUACAAAACCUACACAAUGGAAAAGCCAAACAAAAGAAAAUAAAGUUGGAACUUCUUUCCCUCAUGAGUCCACAUUUGGCGUUGGCAACUUUAAUGCUUUUAAAUCAACUGCCAAGAACUUUAGUCCAUCUACAAAUUCAGUGAAAGAGUGUAAUCGCUCAAAUUCCUCUUCUCCUGUUGACAAACUUAAUCAGCAGCCUCGUCUAACCAAACUGACACGAAUGCGCACUGAUAAGAAGAGUGAAUUUUUGAAAGCAUUGAAAAGAGACAGAGUAGAAGAGGAACAUGAAGAUGAAAGCCGUGCUGGCUCAGAGAAGGAUGACGACUCAUUUAAUUUACAUAACAGCAAUAGUACUCACCAAGAAAGGGAUAUAAACCGAAACUUCGAUGAAAAUGAAAUUCCUCAAGAGAAUGGCAAUGCCUCAGUGAUUUCCCAGCAGAUCAUUCGGUCUUCAACCUUCCCACAAACUGAUGUUCUUUCAAGUUCACUUGAGGCAGAACACAGAUUGUUAAAGGAAAUGGGCUGGCAGGAAGACAGUGAAAAUGAUGAAACAUGUGCUCCCUUAACUGAGGAUGAAAUGAGAGAAUUCCAAGUUAUUAGUGAACAGUUACAGAAGAAUGGUCUGAGAAAAAAUGGUAUUUUGAAAAAUGGCUUGAUCUGUGACUUCAAGUUUGGACCGUGGAAGAACAGCACUUUCAAACCCACAACUGAGAAUGAUGACACAGAGACAAGUAGCAGUGAUACAUCAGAUGACGACGAUGUGUGAAGGAUUUCCUAACAGCUUUAGAAAUCUUAGUGUGAUACAUCUCUCAUACAGUUUGGGGUGAAUUGUAAAAAUGAAGAACUAUAAUUUAUGUAGUGAAAUACCCCAUUAGAAGAGGAUUUUUUGGGGGACUUCAAUAUGAAGAAAACCAAGAAUGUUUUGUUGGGCUGUGUUGAACAUUAUUUCUUUGUAAAUGAAUGUUGUAGGAAUGAGGACUUGGGUUGGUCCAACAUUGACUUUCUUCAUCACUGCAACAUUUCUCUGACUAGCAAUGUGACGAUGUAACAAAUGAGAUUUUCUCAUUUAAUAAUAAAAAAUUGUGUAAUGUUUUGCAAAGCUUCUGUCUUAAAAUGUCCAGGUCUUAAGAAAAAAGGCAGCUUACACUGUUUUGCUUGCAGAGUCAUAUCUUUUUCGUACAAUGGAAAUCCUCAAGUCCACUUUGUGCGGUCUCCCUCUCCUUCCCCCAAAAAACAACAACAACAAAACAAAAACCAAAAAGGAAAAUGUAGCAUGUUGGCUAAAACUGGAGCAAAGUGCACUAAAACAAUUUCCUGAACUCACCUGUUGUACUAUUCACCUUUUAAACCAUAAAUUGCUCUUUAGCCAUUUGUAGUGCAGUAAAUGUUACAGGAAAAGACUUGGCACAUUUUCUUCCAAAUUUUAAGAGGUGAUUUUCAAAAGCUUUAUUGGGGUAUGUUGUCAGACCAGGGUUUUCAGAGUUGAUGGAAAAGAGUCUUGUGAGAAAACUUAUUUUGAUAAAUUAUUACACACGCAGAAAAACUGAUCACACUGACUGGAUCUGUCCACGACAUGGAAAAUAAACUGGAUUUUCAGAAUAUUGUUGUUUUCUGUAGUGUUCAAGGUAUUGUUUCUAAACAUAAACAUACUCUAAACAUGCUUUAUUCACUUGUUAAAGUCAUACUUUUAAAAGUAAUACCUUACUAAAGAUGGUGAUUACUUUUCCGAGGUCAGAAAAGGAAAGCUAAGCGUUUUCAUUAUCAAAUACACAAGCUUAUUAAAUGAAUGACUGUUAACUACUUUAUUUUCAUUUGCACAUUAAUUUUGGAAUUGUUUCUGUUUUGCUGCUGACGGAAAUACUAUUUUGGCUCUGUGUAUAUUUGUAUUUUGAUUUUUCUGGUUUGUUUACCCCCAUUUGCUUUUAGCUCCCCCUUAUGUUUAAAUAUAUUCUAACUUAUGUAAAGAGCAUAAUCUUAGAGCAAAAAUACUUGAGGUUUUAUGUCAGAUCUAAUCUUAAGUGUUUGUUGUUUUUUAAAAAGUGUUUUCUCAGAUGGCUGCAGUGUUUUUGCUAUUUCUGCAUAAAUACCCUACCUGGACUCCCCAGUUUUCACCAGAAACUGUUAUUUUUUUUUGUUGUUGUUCCCACUGAGACUGAUGGUGAUGGGGAAAUUAAAAACAACACACUAGCACACUCCCACAAAACUUGAGGAAGAGUUAGAAUGGUAAUAAAAUAUUAAAUAGACCUUAUACUUAAAAUAAGGUUUCACUAUAUAAUUUGUCACAAUUCAAUCUAAUCAGCUAAAGUUAAAUGUAGUUAGAAUUAGCCACAGGAGAAUGUAAAGCAUGCUUUGACGAAGCUAUCGGUAACACAUAUUGAAUGUCUUUGAGACUCUUAGAUUGUACUAUUUGCUUAAUAGAUUAAUGAAAUUUAUCAGAUACAACCUGUAUUUCCAAAAACAAGCUAGAAGGAACCUGAGGAAUGUGGUUUACAUUUGAGAUCCACCUUACUGUGUUUUCUACUUUCAGAAAAGAUUCUGUAGUUUUGGUUUUUGGCAUCUUUCUUAUACUCAGUUUUUUCUGCCUUAAUUCCCAUUUACCAGCAGUUAACUCAUGUUUAUUGUGCUUUCAUGCAUUGUGAUAUGGAAUGUGUUUAGUAAUUUACUCCUUAUAAAUAUGGUAAAGUACA